AAUUGGGGCCGUACCAUGGCGGAGAAGACUCAAAAGAGUGUGAAGAUUGCUCCUGGAGCAGUUGUAUGUGUAGAAAGUGAAAUCAGAGGAGAUGUAACUAUCGGACCUCGGACAGUGAUCCACCCUAAAGCAAGAAUUAUUGCGGAAGCCGGGCCAAUAGUGAUUGGCGAAGGGAACCUAAUAGAAGAACAGGCCCUUAUCAUAAAUGCUUACCCAGAUAAUAUCACUCCUGACACUGAAGAUCCAGAACCAAAACCUAUGAUCAUUGGCACCAAUAAUGUGUUUGAAGUUGGCUGUUAUUCCCAAGCCAUGAAGAUGGGAGAUAAUAAUGUCAUUGAAUCAAAAGCAUAUGUAGGCAGAAAUGUAAUAUUGACAAGUGGCUGCAUCAUUGGGGCUUGUUGCAACCUAAAUACAUUUGAAGUCAUCCCUGAGAAUACGGUGAUCUAUGGUGCAGACUGCCUUCGUCGGGUGCAGACUGAGCGACCGCAGCCCCAGACACUACAGCUGGAUUUCUUGAUGAAAAUCUUGCCAAAUUACCACCACCUAAAGAAGACUAUGAAAGGAAGCUCAACUCCAGUAAAGAACUAAGAACAGUGUAUAACAUGAAGAUAACAUUUUGUCUUUGACCACUGUCUUUUGAAUGGGCCCACAGUGUUUAUGUACUCUUAACAACUCACAGAAUAAUACAUGUUCACUUUAUUUUGUAAAAUUGGGUUGAGAGGAAACUAAUGGAGUUUCAUUGUAACUGUCCUUUGUAAUUUAUAUAAAUGUAUUAUUUUCCUAUAUCCUUGGUUCUUUUCUGAUAAUUUACAGAUUUAGCUUUUCUUUUGUUAUAUAAACUGCUAGCCACAAAUUUUAGUUAUGUAAAAGGCUACCCUUGACAAGAAAAGACAUACUGUCAUGUAUUUAUAUUCUAGCAUAGACUAAACUGAAUAAAAAUGCUGAUAACAGGACCUUUAGUAAGCAUACUUUAAUCAGUUUUUCUCCUUGAAUUAAUCUUUUCUCUUAAUUUUUAUUAUGUACUAGUUGUAUUAAAGCUAAUGUGUUUACUUUU